ACUCUUCCACCUCCCUUACUGCAGGAAGGCACUCCGAAGACAUAAGUCGGUGAGACAUGGCUGAAGAUAAAAGCAAGAGAGACUCCAUCGAGAUGAGUAUGAAGGGAUGCCAGACAAACAACGGGUUUGUCCAUAAUGAAGACAUUCUGGAGCAGACCCCGGAUCCAGGAAGCUCAACAGACAACCUGAAGCACAGCACCAGGGGCAUCCUUGGCUCCCAGGAGCCCGACUUCAAGGGCGUCCAGCCCUAUGCGGGGAUGCCCAAGGAGGUGCUGUUCCAGUUCUCUGGCCAGGCCCGCUACCGCAUACCUCGGGAGAUCCUCUUCUGGCUCACAGUGGCUUCUGUGCUGGUGCUCAUCGCGGCCACCAUAGCCAUCAUUGCCCUCUCUCCAAAGUGCCUAGACUGGUGGCAGGAGGGGCCCAUGUACCAGAUCUACCCAAGGUCUUUCAAGGACAGUAACAAGGAUGGGAACGGAGAUCUGAAAGGUAUUCAAGAUAAACUGGACUACAUCACAGCUUUAAAUAUAAAAACUGUUUGGAUUACUUCAUUUUAUAAAUCGUCCCUUAAAGAUUUCAGAUAUGGUGUUGAAGAUUUCCGGGAAGUUGAUCCCAUUUUUGGAACGAUGGAAGAUUUUGAGAAUCUGGUUGCAGCCAUACAUGAUAAAGGUUUAAAAUUAAUCAUCGAUUUCAUACCAAACCACACGAGUGAUAAACAUAUUUGGUUUCAAUUGAGUCGGACACGGACAGGAAAAUAUACUGAUUAUUAUAUCUGGCAUGACUGUACCCAUGAAAAUGGCAAAACCAUUCCACCCAACAACUGGUUAAGUGUGUAUGGAAACUCCAGUUGGCACUUUGACGAAGUGCGAAACCAAUGUUAUUUUCAUCAGUUUAUGAAAGAGCAACCUGAUUUAAAUUUCCGCAAUCCUGAUGUUCAAGAAGAAAUAAAAGAAAUUUUACGGUUCUGGCUCACAAAGGGUGUUGAUGGUUUUAGUUUGGAUGCUGUUAAAUUCCUCCUAGAAGCAAAGCACCUGAGAGAUGAGAUCCAAGUAAAUAAGACCCAAAUCCCGGACACGGUCACACAAUACUCGGAGCUGUACCAUGACUUCACCACCACGCAGGUGGGAAUGCACGACAUUGUCCGCAGCUUCCGGCAGACCAUGGACCAAUACAGCACGGAGCCCGGCAGAUACAGGUUCAUGGGGACUGAAGCCUAUGCAGAGAGUAUUGACAGGACCGUGAUGUACUAUGGAUUGCCAUUUAUCCAAGAAGCUGAUUUUCCCUUCAACAAUUACCUCAGCAUGCUAGACACUGUUUCUGGGAACAGCGUGUAUGAGGUUAUCACAUCCUGGAUGGAAAACAUGCCAGAAGGAAAAUGGCCUAACUGGAUGAUUGGUGGACCAGACAGUUCACGGCUGACUUCGCGUUUGGGGAAUCAGUAUGUCAACGUGAUGAACAUGCUUCUUUUCACACUCCCUGGAACUCCUAUAACUUACUAUGGAGAAGAAAUUGGAAUGGGAAAUAUUGUAGCCGCAAAUCUCAAUGAAAGCUAUGAUAUUAAUACCCUUCGCUCAAAGUCACCAAUGCAGUGGGACAAUAGUUCAAAUGCUGGUUUUUCUGAAGCUAGUAACACCUGGUUACCUACCAAUUCAGAUUACCACACUGUGAAUGUUGAUUCUUGCUCCGUCACCCAUGCUCGAGUGCAGUGGCGUGAUCUCGGCACACUGCAGCCUCUGCUUCCUGGGUUCAAGUGAUUCUCCUGCUGCAGCCUCCCAAGUAGCUGGGAUUACAGGUGCACGUCAUUAUGCCCGGGUAAUUUCUGUAUUUUUUAGUAGAGAUGGUGUUUCACCAUGUUGGCCAGGCUGGUCUUGAACUCCUGACCUCUGGUGAUCUGUCUGCCUUGCCUCCCAAAGUGCUAGGAUUACGGGCCUGAGCCACCUUGCCUGGCCUGCAAAAUUUGUUUUUAAUAGAAGACACAAGAAAUGAUUUAAAUAUUUUAUCAACAGAAAACCAGUUCUAUCAACUAUGGGCCCAGUAUGCAGCUUUUAAAAAUGACAGUUCUAUAUACAUUGAUAUGAGACCAUUUCAAACAGGUAUUCAAUAAAGUAUAGAAUGGUAACAUAUCACCAACUGUGUAAAGAAAAAUAUAUAAACAUAUGAAAUGAUACAUUCUGUGCCUAUGCAAACAUAUGAUACAUUAAAAACAAAAGAACAUAUAGUGCCUGUCUCUGAGGGGAACUGUGAAGCUAUGGAAAGGUGUUGAAGAAAACCUUUUUAUAGUAUGUAUUCUUGUAAUUGAAUAAAAAAUAAAAUUACAAAAAUCAGGCUUGGAAGUAUUUAAUAGCAGACAAAAUAUAGUUCAAUAUGAAAAGCAUUAUAUGAGACAAAGGCAAUUUUCAAAAAUUGAUAAAACAUUCCACCAAAAAUCAUGACUACGCAUCUAACAGCUUCAAAAUAUAGAAAAUACUCAAAUGCAAAAUCAACAAAUCUGCAAUUACAGAAAAAGACUUCAACAUACUUUUAGAAAGUAGUAACUCAAGUAGACAAUAAUAGCUAACACUUACCGGGCACUUCUUAUGUGAGUGGCACUGAAACAUGUGCUUUCAUGCAUUACCUAAGGCUAGAGAAAAUGUUAAUAACUUAGACAAGUCAUACAUGUAUCAUAAAUAUCUUUGUACCUGACAAACAGAAUAAACAUCUUUUUAAACACCAUUAGAUAAUUAUUUAAAGACCACAUAUUGGGAACCUACCCCUAAAGAACAAUAACAACCACAAUAACAACUAUCACCCCAGUAAACAUGGCUGGCAAGAAUACAAUUAAAUGAACAUUAUCACUGAUUUGGCAACAGCUCUUAUGAAGAAUAAUUUGGCAUUAUGUAUCAAGUGCCCAUACUCUUUGACAAAGUAACUGUCUUUCUGAUAAUCUAUCUUAAGUAAUACAAAAAUGGGGGGAGGGGAAUAAAAAUACAAAAUAUUAGAAACACUAUCGUCAAAAUGAAAGGGCAUGGCUGAGUAUGGUACAACCGUUCAACAGAAUAUUGUCAUUAAAAACAUUUAUGGAGGCUAUAUUAUAUAGUCAAUAACAGAAAAUGCUUGAAAGGUUAGAAGUACAUCAUCAAAUUAUGUUUUAUAUAGCUGUAAAAUAAACCCAAAUCAUCUUUAAUGAACACAUACUAUUAUGGUAAAAAAAAGUCUACAAUUUCUAACUUUCACCUUAGGCAGCUUUUUAUUUUGCAUCCUUUUUUUCAACUUUGUCUUCUAUUAGCUGUGCAAGAAAUACAUGUCUGCUAAAGUUACACGAUCUUCGCACAACAGCAACCUACACAUUAGUCUACAAAGGGGAACAAACCCAAAUUCCUCAGAAGUCUGAGUCCACUGUUGCCUUCUUUCUGGCCAUCUGGCAGUUACAAUAUAGCACAGAAUGACUAUGCAAGUUAAAUAUUCAUCUUAGACAUGGACAUUUGCUUUGGGACUCCUAAAGUGGAGUCAAAUUUGAUCUCUACAGAAACUCUACAAUGUAGCAGAGCACUGUGCGUACUUAUUGACUCCCAGACAAGCCGAAACCCCGAAUUUGUCAUUUCUAUCAGUUUUUAUAUAAAUUGUUCUUACCUACUUAUUGAUGCUUACAAUUUGGCAAUUAUAAGGGGCAAAAUUGGAGCAAGUGUUUUGGGUAAAUAACUCCUUACAAUAUAUUAAAAAUACUUACAAACAAUUCUUAGAAUCAAACACUUACGUAAAUACUUUUUUAAAAAAAUAGGUCCAAAAGACUCAGCCCAGAUCGGCUUUGAAGUUAUAUCAAGAUUUAAGUCUACUUCAUGCCAAUGAGCUACUCCUCAACAGGGGCUGGUUUUGCCAUUUGAGGAAUGACAGCCACUAUGUUGUGUACACAAGAGAGCUGGAUGGCAUCGACAGAAUCUUUAUCGUGGUUCUGAAUUUUGGAGAAUCAACACUGUUAAAUCUACAUAAUAUGAUUUCGGGCCUUCCCGCUAAAAUGAGAAUAAGGUUAAGUACCAAUUCUGCCGACAAAGGCAGUAAAGUUGAUACAAGUGGCAUUUUUCUGGACAAGGGAGAGGGACUCAUCUUUGAACACAACACGAAGAAUCUCCUUCAUCGCCAAACAGCUUUCAGAGAUAGAUGCUUUGUUUCCAAUCGAGCAUGCUAUUCCAGUGUACUGAACAUACUGUAUACCUCGUGUUAGGCACCUUUAUGAAGAGAUGAAGACACUGGCAUUUCAGUGGGAUUGUAAGCAUUUGUAAUAGCUUCAUGUACAGCAUGCUGCUUGGUGAACAAUCAUUAAUUCUUCGAUAUUUCUGUAGCUUGAAUGUAACUGCUUUAAGAAAGGUUCUCAAAUGUUUUGAAAAAAAUAAAAUGUUUAAAAGUAAAUUAUGGCUUAUAGGAGCUUAUAACUUUAUUCAGAUAGCAUCAAUCAGGGAUGACCAGAACACAUUAGGACCCCAGAUUAUUCAAAAACUUUAACGAAUUUUAAGGGGAAGAAUUUUAUCUUUUCCCUUAAAAUGCAGUCAUAGAAAUUAGAGGAUGACUCACUGCCACAGUGUCUAAAAGCAUUUGCUAGCAAAGAGGCAGGACACUAAUUUGUAAACUGCUCAACUGUUCUGACUGGAAGGGAGGCCUGGAGCUCUGCUAUCACCAAUCCUUCCCUUCCCUCUACUCCACAUCCUUCUAAGGAGCAUGAUUUGAAAAUUACUUUCCUAGGUUAAUGGGCAUGUGCAUCAAUGGAGAGAAUAGUAUAAGCAAGUGAGAUGUAGACUAAGCAAAAUUUAGAUGGAGAAGCACAUUUUAAAAAAUUAAUAACUUAAAAGUCUCAAGUUAUUAAUUUUUUUUUUGCUAACUCAAUUGGAAGUAAGACUAUGAAAUAUUUCAGUGUGUUUCCAAUUCCCAGUUGAAUGCAGUGUUUCAGAAUUUCAGGUAUUUCUUAAGAUCCUCGAAAACACUGGUGCUGUCAAGUCCAAGUUCCUCGUACAGGAAUUUAAUUUGGGCUGUAAUCUAAAAGAAACACAUUAAAAAAAUUAAAUAGAAGGCCUUUGUAGUAAAAUGCCACUGUUUAAGCUUCUCUUUAUCUAUCCAUCUUUACCUAACCGUGAAGUCAGCAAUUUAUGGCAAGAAUACUUUCAUUCGAGAGAGAGGCAGAAGGCUUCCAACAAUUAAGAUUAAAUUAUUUUCUUUAACAGAGCUCACGUAUCAAGUACAAGAGAGAGACAUUUCUCUUGAUUGACACAGUGUCCCUCCCUCCCCUCCUGGGUCUCACCCAUAGAUAGGACAUUUGUGAAGUGGCUUUGUCAUAAACCUGCUGCAACCACUGAAAAUGUGAAAACAACAUGUAUCUAGUUCGGGAAUCUGUCCACUGAGAGGGCCUUGAUAACAUACCUUUUUGUGAGAAUCCUCAAUUACAUGAUUGCCUCCAGGCUGAAUAUCUAGAAUAAUAUUAGGGGUCUGAUAGCCUGGAAGAGUUAACAUGUAGAACAAUUAGAAGAUUGUAUGGGAUCUUCUUUGGAAGAUCGAGACCCAUUCCUCCCCUCUUCUUUGAGUACUCAGUUCAAAUAAUAGUAAAGGAAUAAAAAGCAAAAACCACCAUCAUCAACAAAAAGAUGGGAGGGGACAAGCAACAGAAGACAAACUUCUGACACAGCGAAAGCAGGAAGAGGCCGUAUGGAAAAGACUAUAUGGUGCCACACGGACAAGGUUGAAACCCAGGAGAUCAUCAACCUGCCCUGUGGAAUCUGAGAGUCUUAUGCCCUGGAAACACCAACUACAGCAAUGGAUGGGGGUGACAAAUGGAGAUGAAUACAGGGAGACUGAUAUGGCAUGUAGUUUCAAGGCAAAAGGGAGGGAUUCUUAUCUCAUAAAGCUGAAACAGCUAGCUAGAGGAAAUUCAUGCAGCUAAACAGUUUGGGCACUGAUGGCCCAAAACAAAAAUCUCAGAAUCUGUCUUUUAGAGAUUCCCAAGAAUAACGGCUCAAUAAAUAUUGUUAAAUGAA